ACACACCCAGUGAGGUCUCUGGAGCCGCGGUGCGGGAAGCGGGGACCCGGGUUUGAAUCCUGCCCCUCUGGUGUGGUGCGGCCUCUUCCCACAGACUUUUGGCCUCAGUGUUCCCCGCCUGGGAAGUGGGGACUGGCCCUGGUACCUGGCUCCAGAGCUGCACCCAGAGGCGAUCAGCCCGGUGCGGGAACGGGGCGGGGUGGCCGCAACUACGGGCCACGGAUCCUGACCCGCCCUGCCCACGAUGACUAUCCACAUCCUCAUCCUGCUGUUGCUCCUCGCCUUCUCCGCCCAAGGGGACCUGGACACUGCAGCCAGGCGAGGCCAGCACCAGGUCCCCCAGCACCGCGGGCACGUCUGCUACCUGGGCGUAUGCCGGACCCACCGCCUGGCGGAGAUCAUAUACUGGAUUCGCUGUCUCCACCAAGGAGCCCUCGGGGAAGGCCAGCCACGAGCCCCAGGACCCCUACAGCUAUGGGCGCCGCCGGUGGCGCGAGGCGGAAGCCCGGCUCGGUUCCCAGGAUUCCGGCCUGCAGCGAGGGGGCUAGCGCAGUGCCCAGCUCGCUGGGUGACCUCGGGCACGGCUCGUCCCCUCCUCGGCUUCAGUUUGCCUAUCUGUAUGUUGGAGCUUCUACUCCACAUUUCUUCUCCCCUAACUCCAGCCCCUGAAACCGUCUUCCCCAGUCCCUCCCCGGGCUGCGACUAGGUUGGACCUAGAAGCACACGGGACCAGGCUGGGCGAAGAACACUGACGCCCAGAGCCGAAUAAACAAGAGUUCCGUGUUUCA